GAGUGAGGCCGCUGGCCGGGUCAGAGCGCCGGGGCAAGGCGGGGCUGCGCCAUCAGACCGCUGUCCCGGGCCCUCCGUGUGGCCGCCUUAUGCCAGCGGCCGCCAAGGAAAUGAGCAGGCCUGGCCGGCCCGGGCCCCGAGGGAGGCCAGCCGCGAGCGGAGAGGUCGGCGGUCCGCAGAGCAGGGUCCCGUGGACCGGAGAGCGGGAUGCCGAGGUGCUCAGGAACAGCCCAUGGAAGAAUCAUAUGAAGAGGUGGUGACUGAGGUCGUAAGCAGGAGUGGACAUGUUUGGAUUUCCAACAGCUACCCUGCUGGACUGUCAUGGAAGAUAUGCCCAGAAUGUAGCGUUCUUCAGUGAGUGAGUCAGUUGAUGGCUGGAUGCGCUCAGCUCACAGAUAUUCAGUGUCCCUGUUCUCAGCACUGGUCGGCAGUCUGAGGAAGCAGAGGAGACCUUGCUUUGAUGUGAUGACUGAAGCCCACCACAAAUAUGACCACUCUGAGGCUACAGGAUCCUCAAGCUGGGAUAUCCAAAAUUCUUUCAGAAGAGAGAAGCUGGAACAAAAAUCCCCAGAUUCGAAGACACUACAGGAAGAUUCACCUGGAGUGAGACAAAGGGUCUAUGAGUGCCAGGAGUGUGGAAAAUCCUUCCGGCAAAAAGGUAGUCUAACGUUACAUGAGAGAAUCCACACUGGUCAAAAGCCUUUUGAGUGCACCCACUGUGGAAAAAGCUUCAGGGCCAAAGGCAAUCUUGUUACACAUCAACGGAUACACACGGGAGAGAAGCCUUAUCAGUGCAAGGAGUGUGGGAAAAGCUUCAGUCAACGAGGUAGUCUCGCUGUCCACGAGAGACUCCACACUGGACAGAAACCCUACGAGUGUGCUAUUUGUCAGAGAAGCUUCAGGAAUCAGAGUAACCUUGCUGUUCACAGGAGAGUUCACAGUGGUGAGAAGCCCUAUAGAUGUGAUCAGUGUGGAAAAGCCUUCAGUCAGAAAGGAAGCUUAAUUGUUCACAUCAGAGUCCACACAGGCCUGAAGCCCUAUGCCUGUACCCAGUGCAGGAAGAGUUUCCACACCAGGGGGAAUUGUAUUCUGCAUGGCAAAAUCCACACAGGAGAGACACCCUAUCUGUGCGGCCAGUGUGGAAAAAGCUUCACCCAGAGAGGGAGUCUGGCUGUGCACCAGCGAAGCUGCUCACAGAGGCUCACCCUUUGACCACUUUCCUGAAGAGAAGUUCUCUUUAUGAAUUAAGAGUACAAAAUCCUCUGAGAUGAAGCAACCUAUCCAGUUCUAUGGAAUGAAUGGAGAAUCUUUCAGAAAGACCAUCAUUGGGUAGGGCAAACUGAUUUUUUUCCUUUCCCCCAAAAGAGUAUGAAAAAUAAAUGUCUUGUUUAUUAUCAUUA